AAUGCGACCUCAUCUUUGUCAGUGCACAAAAUGGCGCCCUACAGCCUACUGGUGACUCGGCUGCAGAAAGCUCUGGGUGUGCGGCAGUACCAUGUGGCCUCAGUCCUGUGCCAACGGGCCAAGGUGGCGAUGAGCCACUUUGAGCCCAACGAGUACAUCCAUUAUGACCUGCUAGAGAAGAACAUUAACAUUGUUCGCAAACGACUGAACCGGCCGCUGACACUCUCGGAGAAGAUUGUGUAUGGACACCUGGAUGACCCCGCCAGCCAGGAAAUUGAGCGAGGCAAGUCGUACCUGCGGCUGCGGCCGGACCGUGUGGCCAUGCAGGAUGCGACGGCCCAGAUGGCCAUGCUCCAGUUCAUCAGCAGCGGGCUGUCCAAGGUGGCUGUGCCAUCCACCAUCCACUGUGACCAUCUGAUUGAAGCCCAGGUUGGGGGCGAGAAAGACCUGCGCCGGGCCAAGGACAUCAACCAGGAAGUUUAUAAUUUCCUGGCAACUGCAGGUGCCAAAUAUGGCGUGGGCUUCUGGAAGCCUGGAUCUGGAAUCAUUCACCAGAUUAUUCUGGAAAACUAUGCGUACCCUGGUGUUCUUCUGAUUGGCACUGACUCCCACACCCCCAAUGGUGGCGGCCUUGGGGGCAUCUGCAUUGGAGUUGGGGGUGCCGAUGCUGUGGAUGUCAUGGCUGGGAUCCCCUGGGAGCUGAAGUGCCCCAAGGUGAUUGGCGUGAAGCUGACGGGCUCUCUCUCCGGUUGGUCCUCACCCAAAGAUGUGAUCCUGAAGGUGGCAGGCAUCCUCACGGUGAAAGGUGGCACAGGUGCAAUCGUGGAAUACCACGGGCCUGGUGUAGACUCCAUCUCCUGCACUGGCAUGGCGACAAUCUGCAACAUGGGUGCAGAAAUUGGGGCCACCACUUCCGUGUUCCCUUACAACCACAGGAUGAAGAAGUACCUGAGCAAGACCGGCCGGGAAGACAUUGCCAAUCUAGCUGAUGAAUUCAAGGAUCACUUGGUGCCUGACCCUGGCUGCCAUUAUGACCAACUAAUUGAAAUUAACCUCAGUGAGCUGAAGCCACACAUCAAUGGGCCCUUCACCCCUGACCUGGCUCACCCUGUGGCAGAAGUGGGCAAGGUGGCAGAGAAGGAAGGAUGGCCUCUGGACAUCCGAGUGGGUCUAAUUGGUAGCUGCACCAAUUCAAGCUAUGAAGAUAUGGGGCGCUCAGCAGCUGUGGCCAAGCAGGCACUGGCCCAUGGCCUCAAGUGCAAGUCCCAGUUCACCAUCACUCCAGGUUCCGAGCAGAUCCGCGCCACCAUUGAGCGGGACGGCUAUGCACAGAUCUUGAGGGAUCUGGGUGGCAUUGUCCUGGCCAAUGCUUGUGGCCCCUGCAUUGGCCAGUGGGACAGGAAGGACAUCAAGAAGGGGGAGAAGAACACAAUCGUCACCUCCUACAACAGGAACUUCACGGGCCGCAACGACGCAAACCCCGAGACCCAUGCCUUUGUCACGUCCCCAGAGAUUGUCACAGCCCUGGCCAUUGCGGGAACCCUCAAGUUCAACCCAGAGACCGACUACCUGACGGGCACGGAUGGCAAGAAGUUCAGGCUGGAGGCUCCGGAUGCAGAUGAGCUUCCCAAAGGGGAGUUUGACCCAGGGCAGGACACCUACCAGCACCCACCCAAGGACAGCAGCGGGCAGCAUGUGGACGUGAGCCCCACCAGCCAGCGCCUGCAGCUCCUGGAGCCUUUUGACAAGUGGGAUGGCAAGGACCUGGAGGACCUGCAGAUCCUCAUCAAGGUCAAAGGGAAGUGUACCACUGACCACAUCUCAGCUGCUGGCCCCUGGCUCAAGUUCCGUGGGCACUUGGAUAACAUCUCCAACAACCUGCUCAUUGGUGCCAUCAACAUUGAAAACGGCAAGGCCAACUCCGUGCGCAAUGCCGUCACUCAGGAGUUUGGCCCCGUCCCUGACACUGCCCGCUACUACAAGAAACAUGGCAUCAGGUGGGUGGUGAUCGGAGACGAGAACUACGGCGAGGGCUCGAGCCGGGAGCAUGCAGCUCUGGAGCCUCGCCACCUUGGGGGCCGGGCCAUCAUCACCAAGAGCUUUGCCAGGAUCCACGAGACCAACCUGAAGAAACAGGGCCUGCUGCCUCUGACCUUCGCUGACCCGGCUGACUACAACAAGAUUCACCCUGUGGACAAGCUGACCAUUCAGGGCCUGAAGGACUUCACCCCUGGCAAGCCCCUGAAGUGCAUCAUCAAGCACCCCAACGGGACCCAGGAGACCAUCCUCCUGAACCACACCUUCAACGAGACGCAGAUUGAGUGGUUCCGCGCUGGCAGUGCCCUCAACAGAAUGAAGGAACUGCAACAGUGAGGGCAGUGCCUCCCCGCCCCGCCGCUGGCGUCAAGUUCAGCUCCACGUGUGCCAUCAGUGGAUCCGAUCCGUCCAGCCAUGGCUUCCUAUUCCAAGAUGGUGUGACCAGACAUGCUUCCUGCUCCCCGCUUAGCCCACGGAGUGACUGUGGUUGUGGUGGGGGGGUUCUUAAAAUAACUUUUUAGCCCCCGUCUUCCUAUUUUGAGUUUGGUUCAGAUCUUAAGCAGCUCCAUGCAACUGUAUUUAUUUUUGAUGACAAGACUCCCAUCUAAAGUUUUUCUCCUGCCUGAUCAUUUCAUUGGUGGCUGAAGGAUUCUAGAGAACCUUUUGUUCUUGCAAGGAAAACAAGAAUCCAAAACCA